ACAGUACCUCACAGGUCUCUUCCCCCGAGCAGUGCAUUGCUGGAGCGAGGAGAAGCUCACGAAUCAGCUGCAGGUCUCUGUUUUGAAAAAGCAGAGAUACAGAGGCAGAGGAAAAGGGUGGACUCCUAUGUGACCUGUUCUUAGAGCAAGACAAUCACCAUCUGAAUUCCAGAAGCCCUGUUCAUGGUUGGGGAUAUUUUCUCGACUGCAUGGAAUCAGAAAGAAGCAAAAGGAUGGGAAAUGCCUGCAUUCCCCUGAAAAGAAUUGCUUAUUUCCUAUGUCUCUUAUCUGCGCUUUUGCUGACUGAGGGGAAGAAACCAGCGAAGCCAAAAUGCCCUGCCGUGUGUACUUGUACCAAAGAUAAUGCUUUAUGUGAGAAUGCCAGAUCCAUUCCACGCACCGUUCCUCCUGAUGUUAUCUCAUUAUCCUUUGUGAGAUCUGGUUUUACUGAAAUCUCAGAAGGGAGUUUUUUAUUCACGCCAUCGCUGCAGCUCUUGUUAUUCACAUCGAACUCCUUUGAUGUGAUCAGUGAUGAUGCUUUUAUUGGUCUUCCACAUCUAGAGUAUUUAUUCAUAGAAAACAACAACAUCAAGUCAAUUUCAAGACAUACUUUCCGGGGACUAAAGUCAUUAAUUCACUUGAGCCUUGCAAACAACAAUCUCCAGACACUCCCAAAAGAUAUUUUCAAAGGCCUGGAUUCUUUAACAAAUGUGGACCUGAGGGGUAAUUCAUUUAAUUGUGACUGUAAACUGAAAUGGCUAGUGGAAUGGCUUGGCCACACCAAUGCAACUGUUGAAGACAUCUACUGCGAAGGCCCCCCAGAAUACAAGAAGCGCAAAAUCAAUAGUCUCUCCUCGAAGGAUUUUGAUUGCAUCAUUACAGAAUUUGCAAAGUCUCAAGACCUGCCUUAUCAAUCAUUGUCCAUAGACACUUUUUCUUAUUUGAAUGAUGAGUAUGUAGUCAUCGCUCAGCCUUUUACUGGAAAAUGCAUUUUCCUUGAAUGGGACCAUGUGGAAAAGACCUUCCGGAAUUAUGACAACAUUACAGGUUCAUAAUACAGACAUCUGUGGAUCUGAGAAGUCCUGCAGUGAGGAAAUUUUUCCAAUAUUUUUCACCCUUAAUUUGGCCAUGGAAUUUAAUUCUUUCUUUUCUUUUCUUUUUUCUUUUUUUUUCUUUUUUUUUUUUUUUUUGAGACAGAGUCUCGCUCUGUCACCCAGGCUGGAGUGCAGUGGCACAAUCUCAGCUCACUGCAACCUCCAACUCCCGGGUUCAAGCAAUUCUUCUGCCUCAGCCUCCCAAGCAGCUGGGACUACAGGUGCGUGCCACCAUGUCCAGCUAAUUUUUGUAUUUUUAGUACAGACAGGGUUUCACCAUAUUGGCAAAGCUGGUAUUGAACUCCUGACCUCAUGAUCCGCCCACCUUGGCCUCUCAAAGUGCUGCCAUUACAAGCGUGAGCCACCGCACCCGGCCGGAAUCUAAUUCUUUCUAUGAAAACUUUUACUUAUCUGGAUCUCUCUUUUUUUUUUUUUUUUUUUGAGAUGGAGUCUUGCUCUGUUACCCAGGCUGGAGUGCAGUGGCGUGAUCUGGGGUCAAUGCAACCUCAGCCUCCUGGGUUCAAGCGAUUCUUGUCCUUCAGCCUCCCAAGUAGCUGGGACUACAGGCAUGUGCCACCACGCCCUAAUAAUUUUUUGUAUUUUUAGUAGAGAUGGGGUUUCACCAAGUUGGUCAGGCUGGUUUCGAAUUCCUGGCCUCAAGUGAUCCACCCGCCUUGGCCUCCCAAAGUUCUGGGAUUACAAGAGUAAACCACCUUGCCUGGGCUUACUUAGCUGAUCUCUUAAGUUUCUUUCCCAUUUUAAUAAUUUUUAAAAUUAUAAGUCAUAAGUUAGAACAUAGGGCUCCCUCUACAAUUUUUAAUAUCAGUUUUAGCUUCUAAUACCUUUAAAUCUGCUCUCAAGAGCACUCACACCUCCCCAUAAAAGGUAACCCUUUAGACAAGGCAUGGAGGGUCAUGAUAGAUUUUGCUGGUAGCCAUCACCCUCAUUGCUCAAAGGACCAAGACAGGUCUGGGGCUUGCUUGAGGCUGGGGUUGCUUAAAUAAAGGGAUCCCUUCCAAACUGAGACCCUUUUGGAAUCCUCCUUUCUUUUAGAAUCCUCCUCUCUGAAGGAAGAAGGUCAUGCUUCCUUAGGCCCCCAUAAGUUUUCCAGUGGACUAUAGCAGGGUUUUGUGCGGUCGAAACCAGGCUUUUCUUACUUGUGUAUGGUUCAUCAAUUUCUUUGAAUGACUCUUUAGAUGAGCACUUACAAGAGAAAUAAAUCAUACAUCUGCAAACUUUCUGAGGGCAUCUCAGAGCUCAUCUUGUCUAGGAUGAUGUCUUAGUCCCUUCCUGCUGCUGUAACAAAAAAUACCUUGACUGCGUAAUUUAUAAGAACAGAAAUUUAUUUCUCAUAGUUCUGGAGGCUGGGAACUCCAUGAUCAAGGCACCAGGAGAUUUAGGGUCUGGUGAGGGCUCACUCUCUGCUUCAAAGACGGUGCCUUCUCUGUGUCCUAACAUGGCAGAAGGGCAAAAAAAGAUCUAACAGACUCGCUCAAGCCCUUUUGCAAGGGCACAAAUUCCAUUCAUGAGUGUGGAGUCCUCAUGAUCUAAUCACCUCCUAGACACCCCACUUCUUAAUACUAUUACACUGGGGAUUAAGCUACAACAUAAAUUUUGGAGGGACAGAAACAUUCCAACCAUAGCAGAUGACAAAUAUAUGCCCCAUACUCAGUCAUUAUCCCUUCCUUCACUCUAGACAGGCACCACUAAUCUAUCAUGGGAAUCUUUCAUGUAGAGUGCAGACACGGCCACAGAAUCCUUCUCAACACAGUUCCCCAGACAAUCACACGCAAUGAGCCAAUCAGUAUUGGUACAUGUGUUGGAAUCUGGUGGCCAUCCUUAAUCUAGUCUAAAGUCUCAUUGUACAGAAAAGAAAACUGAGCCUCAGAGAAGUUAAAUGAUUUUCUUAAGAUCAUACAAUCAGUUUAGCCCUGAAAAGAGUCAGAAAUAAAACUAUUUUGCCUAUGGAUGAAGCCAAUUAGUAGAAAGAAUUAAUGUAGAACUUUCUGCCCCGCACUAGCGCUGUAGUCAGAAGAGGCCUAAAGCCCAGAUUUGUUCAGCUGUCUCUGGAUUUUCUAGAGCCAAACUCCUGCAAGAUCAGAAUCUACUGAUAAAUGUCAAACUCUUCCCCAAAGGAUACCAAGCUAGGCCACUGACAGAUCCCACAUCAUUUUCUGUGAUUUUCCAAAAUAACUUUCAGGAGCAGUGCCCAUGGCUGCACCCUUCUUUCGAUUUUUUUAAAGAUUCCUUUUCCUUCUCUUCACUCCUGCCACCAGUGACCUAAAGCUCCAGAAAAGUGACAAGUGGCAUCUCCUUUCUUUGCAGGGGAAAGGCAAAUUAUUCUAGAGCAGGAAGCAGUUCAGACUUAGAGCAAAACAAUUACAGUAGAGCCAUGGGCUACCCAGACCACAACGCUAGCCUUUGGUUAUCUAAGAUCUUAGAUAAACCAAAUUUGAAGUCCUGGAAUAGCUAACUUGUCCCCAGCUUGGGUUAAAAGCAUAGAGAUGCUGGUAGGCCUGGCUUUGAAUCCCCAACUCUGCCUUCUGCUACCAGAACAGCCUCUCUGAGCUUCAGUUUACUCAUGUGGAAAAAGGAUAAUAUUUAUCUCUUAAGAUUGUUGGGAAAAUUAAUGAGGUAAAUUGAGAAAGCACAUAAUAGAUGCUCAGUAAACAGUAGUUUUCAUUAGAAUUAUGAUUAACUCAUUUGUGUCAGGGAAACUAAUGCUUUCUUUCUGCAAGAAGUAAGAGGAGAACACUCGGGCCAUAGCUGUGUGUCCUGAACGUCUAGCGCAGGCUAGAUAUGACAUUAACAACUCAAUUGUUGGCAACAAGGCCCCACGAGGCACAAAGGCACGGAACUUUAGGACACUGCUGCCAUUGGGCUUUGGAGACCAGCCUUGCCUAAUCAACCAAGGAGAUCUCUUGUUUCAGGCUGAUUUGGGUGGAAGUUGUAUGGCCCCAGCCCGCAUGUUUACAUGCUCCAAAAGAGGAUGGCCACACAACUAAUCUCUCCUUUGUCUUUUCCCAGGCACAUCCACUGUAGUAUGCAAGCCUAUAGUCAUUGAAACUCAGCUCUAUGUUAUUGUGGCCCAGCUGUUUGGUGGCUCUCACAUCUAUAAGCGAGACAGUUUUGCAAAUAAAUUCAUAAAAAUCCAGGAUAUUGAAAUUCUCAAAAUCCGAAAACCCAAUGACAUUGAAACAUUCAAGAUUGAAAACAACUGGUACUUUGUUGUUGCUGACAGUUCAAAAGCUGGUUUUACUACCAUUUACAAAUGGAACGGAAACGGAUUCUACUCCCAUCAAUCCUUACACGCGUGGUACAGGGACACUGAUGUGGAAUAUCUAGAAAUAGUCAGAACACCUCAGACACUCAGAACGCCUCAUUUAAUUCUGUCUAGUAGUUCCCAGCGUCCUGUAAUUUAUCAGUGGAACAAAGCAACACAAUUAUUCACUAACCAAACUGACAUUCCUAACAUGGAGGAUGUGUACGCAGUGAAGCACUUCUCAGUGAAAGGGGACGUGUACAUUUGCUUGACAAGAUUCAUUGGUGAUUCCAAAGUCAUGAAAUGGGGAGGCUCCUCGUUCCAGGAUAUUCAGAGGAUGCCAUCGCGAGGAUCCAUGGUGUUCCAGCCUCUUCAAAUAAAUAAUUACCAAUAUGCAAUUCUUGGAAGUGAUUACUCCUUUACUCAAGUGUAUAACUGGGAUGCAGAGAAAGCCAAAUUUGUGAAAUUUCAGGAAUUAAAUGUUCAGGCACCAAGAUCAUUCACACAUGUGUCCAUUAAUAAGCGUAAUUUUCUUUUUGCUUCCAGUUUUAAGGGAAAUACACAGAUUUACAAACAUGUCAUAGUUGACUUAAGCGCAUGAGACACCAAAUUCUGUGGCUGCCAUCAGAAAUUUUCUACAGUACAUGACCCGGAUGAACUCAAUGCAUGAUGACUCUUCUUAUCACACUUGCAAAUGAAUGCCUUUCAAACAUUGAGACUGCUAGAACCAAGCACUACCAGUAUCUCCAUCCUUAACUGUCCAGUCCAGUGAUGUGGGAAGUUACCUUUUAUAAGACAAAAUUUAAUUGUGUAACUGUUCUUUGCAGUGAAGAUGUGUAAAUAAGCGUUUAAUGGUAUCUGUUACUCCAAAAAGAAAUAUUAAUAUGUACUUUUCCAUUUAUUUAUUCAUGUGUACAGAAACAACUGCCAAAUAAAAUGUUUACAUUUUCUUUCAUA